AAGAGAGCUUGGAAGGGAUUGUUCGAGGAUGUGGGAUUUGGUCUUAGAAGACCGAAGGAUGAAUUCCCUGCGCCUGGUCGCCCCCAUGUGGAAUGGGCGUAUCAGGGGCAUCCAUCGCCUGGGUGCGGCAGUGGCCCCAGAGGGCAAUCAGAAGAAGAAAAGGACAAUACUCCAGUUCCUGACCAACUAUUUCUACGAUGUGGAGGCUCUGAGGGAUUACUUGCUCCAAAGGGAGAUGUACAAGGUGCAUGAGAAAAAUCGGUUUCGAGACAAGGAGUGGAUCAGGCCAGAUAAGUAUGGCCAUUUCUCUCAGGAGUUCUGGAAUUUCUGUGAAGUGCCUGUCGAAGCUGUGGAUGCCGGUGACUGUGACAUCAACUACGAGGGCCUGGAUAACCUCCUCCGCCUGAAGGAGCUCCAGUCCUUGUCGCUGCAGCGCUGCUGCCACGUGGACGACUGGUGUCUCAGCCGCCUCUACCCACUGGCCGACUCGUUGCAGGAGCUCUCGCUGGCCGGUUGCCCCCGCAUCUCCGAACGGGGCCUCGCCUGCCUCCACCACCUCCAGUGAGACCUCAGCUCAGGCUGGGCCACAUGCCCAGGCACCUCUCCCACCUAACCCAGAUGCAGGAGAGGAAGUGGGGAGGGGCAAUGUUAGGCAGUUCUCAUAUCCCCCUGCAUCCAUCACAAACCUAGAGUAUUUAUGGUAGAUGAGCAGUCACAGUGAGUCUCUGGAAGAAUUAAAUGACUCCUGGUUUUCUUCCUUUUUGUUUUAGUCAAAACUGUGUGAUAUCGACGCUGUUGCAGAACAGCAGGAGCUGGAGUUGCAUAUUUGCAAUUAACACAGUGGGCUUCAUGUGCCUGGACAGCUAUAAAGAUUUUAUUUUAGGAAGCUAAGGUUGAAAUUUGGGGCCAGUACCUCCCUAUACACACACACAUGCACGCAUGCACGCACGCACACACACACACGCACGCACACACACUGUCCUGUAAGGUUGAAAUUUGGGGCCAGUACCUCCCUACACACACACACACACACACACACACACACACACGCACGCUGUCCUGUACCUCCCUACACACACGCACACGCUGUCUGUACCUCCCUACACACACACACACACACACACACGCUGUCCUUAUACUGGCUUAUCUCCCUAUACACACACACACACACACACACACGCUGUCCUGUACCUCCCUACACACACACACACACAUGCUGUCCUUACACUGGCUUACCUCCCUAUACACACACACACACACACACGCACACACUGUCCUGUACCUCCCUAUACACACACACGCUGUCCUUACACUGGCUUACCUGCCUAUACACACACACACACGCACACGCUGUCCUGUACCUCCCUACACACACACACAUGCUGUCCUUACACUGGCUUCCUGUCCUUCUCACCCCUUUUCAGGAACCUCCGCAGGCUGGACAUCUCGGACCUCCCUGCCGUGUCCAACCCUGGCCUCACUCAGAUAUUGGUGGAGGAGAUGCUGCCCAAUUGCGAGGUUGUGGGAGUCGACUGGGCUGAGGGCCUGAAGUCAGGGCCGGAGGAGCAGCCUCGGGACACAGCCAGCCCUGUCCCUGCCUAGCCUUUAGCCCUGUCCCCACUCACGUGGCUUCUCAGCGGGCUGCAUGGAAUGUCUGGUAGCUCACCACACUUCUGGCUUCCAUUUGUCUUCACUCAACGUCAGGGUGGGGGAGUGGUGCUGGCCAAUCACAGGAGAGAGCGUGAGUUCCCAGUAUUUAUUCCUGGCUGCCCUUGGCUAAAGGUCACAGCUCCUGUCACCCUGUCAGGCAGCCCUUUCCAUGCCCCUGUUCAGGCCUGGGGAGGUAAAGGCUCAGGCUGUUAGUAGCCGCAGAGAGCCACACUCACCUUGUCAGGAGACUCUUCUCAAACUGUCCUUAUGUGAGUGCACUGCCAUUUCUUGCAGGGACCCUGACUGACACAGGGGCUACUACUGACACUUUACAGGGAUGGUUCUCCCCCGUGCAGGGCCGCUGUGCCCACUGCAGGACAUGCAGCAUCCUUCGCCCCACUCCACUCACUAAAGGCCAGCGCACCCCAGGCCCCAUAGUAUUGCUGGUUAUGGAUUUAUUGACUUUAUGUUCCAAAUUCAGCUUUUUCAGUUGGCUGUUUUUUGAAAGGGGAUAAGCUUUGUCAGUAGAGGGCACCAAACAGGCAUUAUAGGAGGAAAGGCGCCUCCUUCGUGGUUCUUGUUGGUUGUGCUUCUGCCUCUGGACGCCGCAGUGCAUGUGGCUUCCCCAGCACCCAGCUCCUGAAGCACCAGGCGGUCAGCAGCUGCCCUUGGCACCCUCCAGCCCUCAGAAGUUGCGUAGGAGACACAGCGCCUCCACUGAGGCACCUCUCUGGGAAUAACGUUCCCCAGCACCCCAAAUGGAUUUCCAGUCAAUUCAGAAGCAUUUUACCAGUGAAGCCCUCAUUAUUCCAGUUCACUGUUAAAGCCAGUAAUUCUCUAUAUUAAACUUUCCCUGUUCAAGUUA